GAGGUGCAGCCGGCGCUGAGCGCGGCAGGCGCGGGAGCUGGCGCUGGAGCCGGAGCGGCGGCGGCGGCAGCAUUCACCGGGCGGCGGCGGCGCGGGCUCCGGCACCGGCUCGGGCUCCGGCAUGGUGCAAUCCGGCCUCGUCCCGGGAGAGCAGGGCCCGUGCGCAGGGCCGGCGCCCGGGGAGCGGCGGCAGCGGCGGUGGCGGUGGUGGCUGCAGGCGCAGGCAGGCGGCAGGUGCUAGAAGCGGGGCUGGGCGAGGUGUGUGCCCGCUGGGCUCCCGGGCCGCCGCCCCCUCACUGCCCAGGUCUUUCCCUCCCUUCGUGCUCCCCAGCGCGUCCAGCCCCCUGCCUCCGCGCCUCGGCCCAUGGCGCCCCGCGGCUGAGACAGCGCCGCCAGGGACCCCUCCCGCGGGCCUCCCCGGGGCGUGCAGAUCCCGGAGCCGCCCGCCCACCCUCCGCGAAGCCUCCCUCCCCUCCUCGCCCGAGCCGGGCGGGACCAUGGCUGCGAAGCUGCGAGCGCAUCAGGUGGACGUGGACCCGGACUUCGCGCCGCAGAGCCGGCCGCGCUCGUGUACCUGGCCCCUGCCGCAGCCUGACUUGGCCGGCGACGAGGACGGAGCGCUGGGCGCAGGGGUGGCCGAGGGCGCCGAGGACUGCGGGCCGGAGCGCCGGGCUACGGCCCCGGCGAUGGCCCCAGCGCCGCCCCUGGGCGCGGAGGUCGGACCGCUGCGGAAAGCGAAGAGCUCUCGGCGGAACGCGUGGGGGAACCUGUCCUACGCCGACCUCAUCACCAAAGCCAUCGAGAGCGCCCCGGACAAGCGGCUCACGCUCUCGCAGAUCUACGACUGGAUGGUCCGUUACGUGCCCUACUUCAAGGAUAAAGGCGACAGCAACAGCUCGGCCGGCUGGAAGAACUCCAUCCGGCACAACCUGUCGCUGCACACCCGUUUCAUCCGCGUGCAGAACGAGGGCACCGGCAAGAGUUCGUGGUGGAUGCUGAACCCCGAGGGCGGAAAGACAGGGAAGACCCCGCGGCGCAGGGCCGUGUCCAUGGACAACGGGGCCAAGUUCCUGCGCAUCAAGGGCAAGGCGAGCAAGAAGAAGCAGCUGCAGGCGCCCGAGCGAAGCCCGGACGACAGCUCCCCGAGUGCGCCCGCCCCGGGGCCGGUGCCUGCCGCAGCCAAGUGGGCCGCCAGCCCCGCCUCGCACGCCAGCGACGACUACGAGGCUUGGGCCGACUUCCGCGGCGGCGGGAGACCCCUGCUCGGGGAGGCGGCCGAGCUGGAGGACGACGAGGCCCUGGAGGCCCUGGCGCCAUCAUCGCCGCUCAUGUACCCAAGCCCCGCCAGCGCGCUGUCGCCGGCGCUGGGCUCGCGCUGUCCGGGUGAGCUGCCCCGCCUGGCCGAGCUGGGAGGCCCGCUGGGCCUGCACGGCGGCGGCGGCGCGGGGCUGCCCGAGGGCCUGCUGGACGGCGCGCAGGACGCGUACGGGCCGCGGGCCCGCGCCAGGCCCGGCCCGGUGCUGGGUGCGCCGGGGGAGCUGGCGCUGGCGGGCGCAGCCGCCGCCUACCCCGGCAAAGGGGCGGCCCCGUACGCGCCGCCCGCGCCCUCGCGCAGUGCCUUAGCCCACCCCAUCAGCCUUAUGACGCUGCCCGGCGAGGCGGGCGCCGCGGGCCUGGCACCGCCGGGCCACGCCGCCGCCUUCGGGGGCCCGCCCGGCGGCCUCCUGCUGGACGCUCUGCCGGGGCCCUACGCUGCCGCCGCCGCCGGGCCGCUGGGCGCCGCGCCCGACCGCUUCCCGGCCGACCUGGACCUCGACAUGUUCAGCGGGAGCCUCGAGUGCGACGUGGAGUCCAUCAUCCUCAACGACUUCAUGGACAGCGACGAAAUGGACUUCAACUUCGAUUCGGCCCUGCCUCCGCCGCCGCCGGGCCUGGCCGGGGCCCCGCCCCCCAACCAGAGCUGGGUGCCGGGCUGAGGGCCGCCUCCCGCCUCCGGGCGCCCCGUCCCGUCCCCAGGGGGCCUCUGUCUUCCCAUCCUGAUUCCCGGGUCCCUGCCCCCGACUCUAGCUCCCCAGGAGGCGGCCCCAGCCCAGCUAGGGACCCCUCUCGGAGGCCGGCCGCCGGGGAAGGGGAGGGAGGGGCCGGGGCACCCCACUGCUCCUGCCCACACUCCUGAGAUCCACCCCCUUCUCCUGGGCAGGAAGCCUGGGAGAGGAGGCUGAAUUCCAGGCUGGCUGGGAGUAGGGAGGAGCGGGGUGGGCCGCCUGGUGUGGACGGUGGUCGGGGAAGCCAACUAGGAGAUGGGCCAGGGAGCGUUUACAAAUCUUCAGUUUCAUUUGCGGAGGCCUAGCCGUGACCCCGCGCCCACCCCAAACACGGAUCUGAUUCCCACUUGACACACUUUCCCACUGGUCUUAGUCUCACCCACCCGAAGCCAGCAACCCUCUGCGGAAAACUCACACCUACCUAUAUCCAUCCACCCUGAGCAGCCCUCCACCCCCAAAUCGCCCUCCGACGACCGCCACCCCCACAGUUCAGUCUCCCCCUCCCAUCCCUGCCGGCCCUCGCUUCUCCCCUCCCCCGUCGGAGUCAGUCCCUCUCUUCAACCGCCCCCACCCCCUAGUACUGGUCUCAGCUUCUGCAGCGGGCCUCAGCCCCGUCCACCCCCAACCCCGACGCCCCUUUCUCCGCGCCAGUUCUGGCCCUUCUCCCAUAUUUAUAAGUGUCCGGCCGGGACGGGCGGUGGGCGCGGCGUCCCCGGCGCGUAUCGUAGGCAGUGUACCGUGGCCGUGCCGUCAGAGUGUGCGUGUGCGUGUGUGCCGUGUCGAGGCUGUGUAGAGUGCAUUGUACAGCAUAUUUUCAUGAAUAAAAUUGUUUUAAAUAUU